GAAACAUGCGGCCUCCCGGACUCCUCUCUGUGUCACCGACCUCUUGCGCUCAGUUCUCCGGAGCUGCCGGUUUAACCUCGCAAGUCUUCCCGGAACCCGUGCCCUCCUCCUGGGCAGCGUUACCACCACGAGCGCCUACCUGAGAGGACGCCUGUUCUCAUCCAGCCUCCACCCUGCAGCCGAGCAAUCUCCGUAAAACGAACACCUGGCUUAGUUUCUGCUGGAAACCGUUGAAUAGUCCCCACUGUCUUCUGGAAGGGUCUGGGCAGCUCGGCGUGGCGUCCACGGCCCCACCAGGCCUCUGCCUCCUGCAGGUCCCGCUACUUCGUCACCAAAGCGCCCGCCGCGCUCGCAUCUGCUGUGAGGCUGUGCUCGGGCCGCUCCCGCCGAGGGAACGGCCCUCCCAAGGCUCUGCGCCCCAAUUCUCGCUCGUUUGCCAAGAGGUAGCCGUGUCGGGGAGCUAGAGUUCUCCGGGGACUCUCUCCUGCCCCUCGUGGCCCUCUGUGGAACCCUCGUUUUAGGAUCUGCACGCCGUUUCCAGUCGCGCGCGCGGCACGGAGACCGCCCGCUGUGCCCCGCGCUGCGCUCUCUCCGCCCCUCUCCCGCGCAGGCCUCCCUGUGCCAGCCGGCUGUCGACCCAGGUUAGGAAGCCCGAGGUCGGGGCGUUACCCCAAGGGCCCUCCCGCUUCCCCUCCGAGGGCAGAGAGGCGUCCGCGCCCGGACGCACUGCGGGAACACCUGGAGCGCCGGCGGAGCUCGGCUGUCCCCGCGGGAGGGAGCCCGACGCGCAUCCUUGGGACCCGGACCCGGCGCCCGCGCCUCGGGACGGAUUUCUGCCUCGGCUGCAGGCGCAGCGCGCAGACCUGAGCCUGCCCCGCGGAACCGGGGCUCGAGUCCCGGCCCGAGCGCGGCGUCGGGGCCAGCGGAGAGGGGCGGAAGCCGCAAGGGACCCUCGGCGCCUCGGCCUGGCCGCGAUGAAGUCCCCGCCCCUCCUCAGGUGACGGAUCGCCGCUGCCGUCCCGGGCUGCCCACCACCCCGGCGCGUGCCCGGGAGCCUCCACCCUCCCCGGGUUCUGUGGCCGGCCACGCGCCCCAGGCACGCGCCGCGCCGGGCCGCGCCACCAAGCCCGCUGUCCCCAGCUUUCCUCGGCAGAUCCCCUGGCUACCCCCACCCUGCGGAGGGGCCGUUCACCAGAUGCCAGAAAAUCAGGGUGGGGCACGCAGGCCAGGGGCUCCAGCGGCUGGGCACCGUGUCCUUCCCGAACCUGGUGCUGGAAGUGCGCCCGCCUCCGCCUCUCCCAGGCACCCACCGGCACUGCCCAGCCCUGUCUGGAGGGUCUAGGACUGAACGUCUGUCCCCGGCCUUCAUCCUGGCUGCAGAGGACUGGCCGGGUGAUGCCGCGCUGUCCUGGCCCUGGGCCCGCCUGGAAGACCCGCCUGUGUCGCGGGCCCCCUCCCUGGCUCUGGCCUCUAAAGCGCCCCCGGCACAGCUUCCCGGCCCUUGCAGCCCGGUGGGGCCGGAACCUUCCCCUUGUCACUGUUGUCCUUUCUCCUUUCAGCCCGUGUCUCUCCUGGAAGAGAAUGGCGGGCAUCUUUUUCCUGCCAUUUAUCUCAUCAGGUUUUGCUCCUCGGUUUAAGCAGGAAGAGAACUUCAUGCUUGGAAGAGCGCAUCCGUCCCAGCCUAGGUUUAAUUGGUCUCAUCUGACCCCUCUGGAGCUGAAGAAUCGAUCUGUGGGACUUGGAACUGAAAGCACAGGUCGGGGUAAGCCCCACUUCACACUGGAGGGCCACAAGUUCCUGAUCUUCGGGGGCUCCAUCCACUAUUUCCGGGUGCCCAGGGAGUACUGGAGGGACCGCCUGCUGAAGCUGAAGGCCUGUGGCUUCAAUACUGUCACCACCUAUGUUCCGUGGAACCUGCAUGAGCCAGAAAGAGGCAAAUUUGACUUCUCUGGGAACCUGGACCUGGAGGCCUUCGUCCUGAUGGCCGCAGAGAUCGGGCUGUGGGUGAUUCUGCGUCCAGGCCGCUACAUCUGCAGUGAGAUGGACCUCGGGGGCUUGCCCAGCUGGCUCCUGCAAGACCCCCGGUUACUGUUGAGGACAACCAACAAGAGCUUCAUUGAAGCAGUUGAGAAGUAUUUUGACCACCUGAUUCCCAGAGUGAUUCCUCUCCAGUACCGCCAGGCAGGCCCUGUCAUCGCGGUGCAAGUGGAGAAUGAGUAUGGCUCAUUCAAUAAGGAUAAAACAUACAUGCCGUAUCUCCACAAGGCCCUGCUGAGAAGAGGGAUUGUGGAGCUUCUCUUGACCUCUGAUGGUGAGAAACAUGUGCUGAGUGGCCACACCAAAGGAGUGUUGGCCGCCAUCAAUUUGCAAAAACUUCACCAGGAUACUUUCAAUCAGCUUCAUAAAGUCCAGAGAGAUAAGCCCCUUCUGAUUAUGGAAUACUGGGUCGGCUGGUUCGACAGAUGGGGAGAUAAGCACCAUGUUAAAGAUGCAAAGGAGGUUGAACAUGCUGUGUCUGAAUUCAUCAAAUAUGAGAUCUCCUUCAAUGUAUAUAUGUUCCAUGGUGGAACCAACUUUGGUUUCAUGAACGGGGCCACAUAUUUCGGGAAGCACUCGGGCAUUGUCACCAGCUAUGACUAUGAUGCAGUGCUCACGGAGGCUGGAGAUUACACAGAAAAAUAUCUGAAGCUUCAAAAACUCUUUCAAUCUGUCUCAGCAACUCCCCUGCCCCGAGUACCCAAACUUCCUCCCAAGGCUGUGUAUCCCCCCGUGAGACCGUCGCUGUACCUCCCGCUGUGGGACGCCCUAUCCUACUUAAAUGAGCCAGUCAGGUCGCGUCAGCCCGUCAACAUGGAGAACCUUCCCAUAAACAAUGGGAGCGGCCAGUCCUACGGGCUUGUCCUGUAUGAGAAGUCCAUCUGCUCCGGAGGCCGCCUCCGUGCCCACGCUCAUGACGUGGCACAGGUGUUUUUGGAUGAGACAAUGAUAGGGAUUCUGAAUGAGAAUAAUAAGGACCUGCACAUUCCUGAACUCAGGGACUGCCGAUACCUGAGGAUCCUGGUGGAGAAUCAAGGACGAGUCAAUUUUUCAUGGCAAAUACAGAAUGAGCAGAAAGGAAUAACUGGAUCUGUCAGCAUCAAUAACUCUUCCCUGGAGGGCUUUACCAUCUAUUCCCUGGAGAUGAAAAUGAGCUUCUUUGAGAGGCUCCGCUCUGCCACCUGGAAGCCUGUCCCAGACAGCCACCAGGGCCCGGCCUUCUACUGUGGGACCUUGAAGGCUGGCCCUUCUCCCAAGGACACCUUCCUGAGCCUGCUGAACUGGAAUUAUGGAUUUGUGUUCAUCAAUGGACGUAACCUUGGGCGAUAUUGGAAUAUUGGGCCUCAGAAAACACUGUACCUUCCUGGAGUUUGGCUUCAUCCAGAAGACAAUGAGGUAUGUCACUCCAGUCUCUGCCUUGAGAUCUCAUAAACUUUCAGAUCAAAAUGUGUAACAUCUGCAACAUCUAAACUUAACAACAACCAUGCAACAUAUCCAUUUUACAGAUGAGAAACCAAGGUUCAAAGAGGUAUUUGAAAUCAUGUCUCUCUGAUUGGCACCUCCUCUUUCGCUACUACCUUAGUUCCACACGUAUGCCAGUCUUUUCCAAAUAUGAAUGCAAAAAUGCUAUUCAGAAGAUAUAAUGCUUUCAGUGCACUUAGAGAAAAAGAGCUCACAACUUAGAAUUCUUUACCCAGCAAAACUAUUUUACAAGAAAAACAAAAAAAAAAAACAAAAUAUAGAACUUUCUGACAAACAAAAACCAAGAGAGUUAUCAUCAAAAGAUCCCCACUAAAUGAUGUUCUGUAGCGGCCUUUCUCAAUGUCCCAUAAGAGAAUUAAACACUGCAGAAAGUGUCUUCAGUGACUAGUUUCUCAUUAUAUCAUCUGGAUGCAUAUUAGAGACGUUAACUCAUUACAUACUGUGGAUGUCUUGGGGCAUUACAUCUUCACGCUCUCAGGGAACCACAGUUGAGAAGAAAUUUCUAAAAGAUAUGCCACGAGCAGAUGGAAAGUCUGACUUUUAAGAAAGAACGUGGAAUCCAAGAAGGAUGCUGACAUAUGUGAGAGUGAAUAUGGACAAACGUUAACUCCAUAGAAAUAGAGCCAAUGUCUAACUUGAGGUAGCAUCAGCAUAAAACUCUAAGACCAGGCAAAAACACUGUGUAAAGCGAGAGGGAUGUGAUGGCCAAAAAGUGAUCUAAGAUUUCUGUAAUUCUCAGAUAUUAACUUUAGACUUUGUUGAAUAUUCCUAGUUAAUAAACUAAGCUUAAUGUUUAAAGAAUAUACAUAGAGCUUUUAACUUUCUAAAAAAAUUAGGAGGAUAAAUAGAGUAAGAAAAAACAAACAAA